AGGGCUGGGGAGGGCGCUCCAGGGAAGCCGACCUAGCGUCGAUUCCUGCAGUUGCGGCCCGGGUCCCCGCGCCUGGAGAGGAGGCGACGCGUGGCCGGCGGCUUUGUGGCGCGCGGGUUCCAGCGCGGGGGCGGGGAGAGGGCGAGCUGAGGGCCUCGAGUCCCAGCACUCCGCCACGCUGCGGGCGCCGGGCAUGGCCAGCCCCUUGCCGUCCGGCUUCCCCGCGCGCAGGAACAGCCGCCUGGAUGUGUUCCUGCGGCGGCAUCUGCCGCCCGAGGUCUACGACGCGGUCCGCGCCUACGAGCCAUGCAUCGUGGUGUCCAACUCUGAGAACCACAUCCUCAAGUAUGUGGUGCUAAGCGACCGGCUCGUCUACCUAACCGAGAACCCGCCCAAGUCCAUCCGGCGGGUAGUGGCUCUGCGGGACGUCGUGGCCAUUGACCUGAUUGAUGAUUACCCGGAAUUUUUGAGUUCGCCAGAUAGAGAAAUCAGCCAACACAUUCGUAUCAUCUAUUCUUCAACCGUUUUGAAAAAAGAGUGUAAAAAGUCAAACAGUGUCAGGAAAUUCCUAUUUCCAUUUCAUCAUACUAAAGCUAACAACAAGAAAGUCAAGGAAGAAAAGAACGGCCUUGCCUUUUGGAGAAGCAAAGAGUCCAGAAGUCUGAAAGAAUCUCCUCUCAGGGACCAGCAGGAGAGCAGUACACCAUCCAAGGACUCAACUCUCUGUCCUCGUCCAGGCCUCAAAAAGCUGUCCCUUCAUGGCCAAGGUGCCUUUCGACCCCUACCUUCCCCCUCCAGGAGGAGCUCUCAGUCUGCACCAACAACUGGCAAGGCUGUCAGCGAGCCAUCUUGCACAACAAACACAAAAGAACCCCAGGGACUUCCAGAUCACAACUCCAUAAGUGAAAUUCCUUUCAAGUGCAAUGGGAAUGGAAAUGAGUUUUACUUAGGAAAUUCCCUCUUAGAUUCCCCUUCACAGAGCAACUCAAAUUUAGAGAAAAAGGAGUCAGAACUUCAUUUGUAUGUUAUUUCCACAACCUCAUCAAUAUUUCUGCACUUAAAAAGUUCAUGGAACAAUUAUAUUAUAAAAGCUACUCUUUUACAAGAUCCCUUCUAUGCUAGUGAGUUCAGUCCUGCUAUUGGAAGUCAAAAGCCAUAUAGGUCUGAGGAGAAAAUUAAGCACUUCAGUCAACUUAAAUCUGAACUUUUUCUUAAAGACAAUUCUUUGAGGAGGAUACUUUCUUUACUUAUGGAACUUAAAGUAGCAGCCCAGAAAAACUUCAUUCUGAAAAGGCUUUUCUGGAAGACCAGUGACCUUUUCUAUUUCAUAGUAAACAAACUUCAUGAGUACUUGCCGGAGUCUAGGGAUAAGAAUGCACUACAAAAUCAAAGCCAAAGGGUUGAUGAGCUGGUGGCAUGCAUUGAAAUUAUACAGACCCUAGUAUUGAUGUUCAGAGAAACAGAAACCGAGUCAUCACGCCUGAACACAUUGGCAGCUAAGAAGGGAGCACUAUUUAAUCUCUUGGUAAUUUUAAUUAGUGAGCCUCAGAUUCCAAAAUCUUGUCCUGUGUUUGAUAUCCAGUUGGUGGCUGAUUCAGCUUUAGUCAGAAUGUCUUUUGACGCUGAGUUACAGAAGCUUAUUCUGGAGUAUACAAAUACUGCUACAGCACUUUUAUAUGAGAUACUUCUGGUCUUUCAGCAGGGAAAUCUCGGAUUGGGAUCCACAAAGUUUGCUAUUAGCUGGAUAAUGUCCUUUCUACAAAGCUGUCCUCCCAUCAUUACUUUUGUGGCCAGUAUUGUGAAACAAGUGGUGAGGGGUCUUUCAGCUUCAUUUCAGCUGCUAAGUCCCUGCCAAGCAGUUCUGUUGUACCAGCAAUUUUACAUCCUCAAGAGCUGUCUGCGGCACAGCAGGACUCUAGCUGAGUAUAUUAGGAAUAACUACAGAGAAGAAUUCAGGUACUUUAUUCACAUGCCAGCCUUGCAGAAAAGGCUCCCAUUGUGUUACCCCAUCACUCAACCUACCAUUCAACUUUUUCAUGAAGUUCUGAAAUUGGUUGAAUAGAAACAAACAAUGUACGCAAUGUUAAUAAGAGUAUAAAAUGUUAAUCAAGAGUCAACUUGAUAUUCACGAGAAACAUUUUUUUAUUUGUUUAAUAUCUGGCUAUCUCUGAGUCCUAUAAACAAAGAUUUUAAUUGAAUGUUCCAUCAAUACCUCUCUAUGAGAAGUUUAAAAUUUUAAAAAAUAAAUUUGAUUUAUUAUAAGUGUGCAAAGAUCUUUAUGCCAUUGGGCAAAAGAGCCAUUUCUUUAUUAGAGUAGUUCUUCAAACUCACUCUUGCCACAAAAUAAACGACUAUCCAUCAAGACACAGGAAAAAGGAAUGCAGGGAUUUAGGAAAGCUGUACUCACUUCUCUUCCACCUUAGCAGCAAAAGCAAGAAGGUUCUCAAAAUUCUCCUGAUAAUAGUUCUGUUGCUUAAGCAAUAGGAUGCCGGGGAGUGUGGGGGCCUGAGGCAUGGGCAUUCAAGUUCUUCUCAAGGUGUUUUAUCUUCUCAGCUUGGGCACAGUGUUCUCGGUGAAACCAUGCCAGGCACAGGAGCAUGCUCUUCACCCGAUUCUGUACUCAGAGCCAUCCAAAAACCAUUAUUUCGACUAGGUUCUUGGAGUCCACUAUGUCCACCACCAGCAGGGCCUGGCGCAUCCACGCCACUUCUGGAAUUACAGCUUGGUCUGGGCCUAAGGUCACUCACUCAAGAUCUCAUCCGCCAGCCACGCCUCCAGGUAGAACACCAAAGGGUCUCUCAGUUCCUGCACCAGAAACCACCAAGGCCGGAGGCCAGAGUUUUAAAAUCUGCUACAAAGAAACCUACAUCCAUUCUGACAUACAUAAAGUGGUGCUAAACAGUAGCGUUUCUCCAGAAAAAAAGGUUCUAAGACAAAAAUCUAUCAAGGGAACAGAAGCCUAUGGAGAGUGAACACAGAAAAUAUAAUCUGGUGAGUUUCACUGGUGUAAUAAUGGUGAGUGGUGUGAAGCCACGAAACAUCCUGAGAUAAACUGUUGUGGGGAGUAUAAGCUACAGAGUGAUUAUUUGGGAAAUGCUGAGCAAUAGGAUGACACCCUCCUCCUCCACCUAUACAAAUUCUAGUGACAAAAGUAUUCCUGGAAGAAUGAGCAGAACACAGGCAUAGCUGUAUAGAAUGUCACUUCCUCUUUUAUCAUAGAGAAAGAAGCUUGGACUUCAACAAAAUUAAGUGCAUGGUGCCACUCUGUUUCAGGCAUCUGUGGGCUAAUUUGUGUAGUCCCAUAGAGUCUCUAUGAAAGAUAAAUUGUCUACGAGCAGUUAUGGCUCUCCCACAACCAUUUAAAAACUUGUCUUUACUAUAUUUUAUGCCAUAAACUAAUUUAAUUCCACAAAUACUUAACUUUGGCAUCACCGUGAGGUGUUGAAUUUGGACUUCUAAGAACAUAGGAACUGGACUCUCCAUUCAACUUAUUAUGACUUGAGGGAGGAUCAGAGAAAAAUCUACUUCCAAAGAAAGAGUUCCUAAGCCAGAUUCGCCUGUGUUGGGCAGUGGAGAUAAUUACUAGGACAUUUUAUUCCAGGUUCUGACAGAGCCAAAUGACCAGCUAUUUGACUUCAAGCAAGUCAGGCCCCCUUUCCAGGCCACAUCUGUUUCUUCCUGGGCUUCCUCUGCUAGGUGGAAGGGUGGGACUAGAUGUUCUCCAAGUUCUCUUCCAGCUCUUACAUUCUCUGCCUGUGACAAGACAUUUAACACUCUGAAAUGGAGUAGUGUGUUUCUCUGCUAUCUCGGCUCAGUGGAUGAUUUUGCACUAACUUCAAGUAAUCCUCCUUUCUUUUUACCCAAAGUUUCCCUUUCAGCUGUCACCAGCCAUCACCCCAUAAAGUGUCCAAGUCUUUUCCUUCAUUACCCAAUGAGGAGUCCACAUUUUCUACCCUCAAUUUUGGGGGCAGAGAGAGAGGAGCAAAAUGGUGUUUUUGAGUGUCCUGGCUGUUAGAUGGGGGAUUAUUUUCAAGAGACGGUCAAUCAAAGGAAUAUGAAAAGAUUCUUGGAACAUAGGCAAGUAUUACCUCAAACCGGACAAAGAAUGUACUGAUGAACCCGCAGGAUGACAACGAGAGGAUCAACUCAGCUCUGCCUUAGCUUCUCCGCAGUGCCCUGGAUCUGGGCUAGUAGUCAUGCAGGCUCUAGUGAGGGCUUGGGGUUUCUCUCCCACAUGAUUUCUGCAUGCCUCUCCCACUCCUCUCUUUGCCCUGGGAUCUUACUUUAAUCUCUGGGAGCAAAAUCUCUGUCAAAAUAUAUCUGAAUCUUUUUAUGUGGGGCUAAAGUCAGUGGUUUUUUGGAGAGUUAAUGGUUGAAUAUUUGUCACCCUGAUUUUCUUCAGUCUACUCUGUAUAACUCAUGUCUAUUCAUUUGCACAGUCUGGGAUCAGAAACUAAUAAUUCGAAGGAUUGUCCAACCACUA